AGAUGUGAAUAGCUCCACUAUACCAGCCUCGUCUUCCUUCCGGGGGACAACGUGGGUCAGGGCACAGAGAGAUAUUUAAUGUCACCCUCUUGGGGCUUUCAUGGGACUCCCUCUGCCACAUUUUUUGGAGGUUGGGAAAGUUGCUAGAGGCUUCAGAACUCCAGCCUAAUGGAUCCCAAACUCGGGAGAAUGGCUGCGUCCCUGCUGGCUGUGCUGCUGCUGCUGCUGGAGCGCGGCAUGUUCUCCUCACCCUCCCCGCCCCCGGCGCUGUUAGAGAAAGUCUUCCAGUACAUUGACCUCCAUCAGGAUGAAUUUGUGCAGACGCUGAAGGAGUGGGUGGCCAUCGAGAGCGACUCUGUCCAGCCUGUGCCUCGCUUCAGACAAGAGCUCUUCAGAAUGAUGGCCGUGGCUGCGGACACGCUGCAGCGCCUGGGGGCCCGUGUGGCCUCGGUGGACAUGGGUCCUCAGCAGCUGCCCGAUGGUCAGAGUCUUCCAAUACCUCCCGUCAUCCUGGCCGAACUGGGGAGCGAUCCCACGAAAGGCACCGUGUGCUUCUACGGCCACUUGGACGUGCAGCCUGCUGACCGGGGCGAUGGGUGGCUCACGGACCCCUAUGUGCUGACGGAGGUAGACGGGAAACUUUAUGGACGAGGAGCGACCGACAACAAAGGCCCUGUCUUGGCUUGGAUCAAUGCUGUGAGCGCCUUCAGAGCCCUGGAGCAAGAUCUUCCUGUGAAUAUCAAAUUCAUCAUUGAGGGGAUGGAAGAGGCUGGCUCUGUUGCCCUGGAGGAACUUGUGGAAAAAGAAAAGGACCGAUUCUUCUCUGGUGUGGACUACAUUGUAAUUUCAGAUAACCUGUGGAUCAGCCAAAGGAAGCCAGCAAUCACUUACGGAACCCGGGGGAACAGCUACUUCAUGGUGGAGGUGAAAUGCAGAGACCAGGAUUUUCACUCAGGAACCUUUGGUGGCAUCCUUCAUGAACCAAUGGCUGAUCUGGUUGCUCUUCUCGGUAGCCUGGUAGACUCGUCUGGUCAUAUCCUGGUCCCUGGAAUCUAUGAUGAAGUGGUUCCUCUUACAGAAGAGGAAAUAAAUACAUACAAAGCCAUCCAUCUAGACCUAGAAGAAUACCGGAAUAGCAGCCGGGUUGAGAAAUUUCUGUUCGAUACUAAGGAGGAGAUUCUAAUGCACCUCUGGAGGUACCCAUCUCUUUCUAUUCAUGGGAUCGAGGGCGCGUUUGAUGAGCCUGGAACUAAAACAGUCAUACCUGGCCGAGUUAUAGGAAAAUUUUCAAUCCGUCUAGUCCCUCACAUGAAUGUGUCUGCGGUGGAAAAACAGGUGACACGACAUCUUGAAGAUGUGUUCUCCAAAAGAAAUAGUUCCAACAAGAUGGUUGUUUCCAUGACUCUAGGACUACACCCGUGGAUUGCAAAUAUUGAUGACACCCAGUAUCUCGCAGCAAAAAGAGCGAUCAGAACAGUGUUUGGAACAGAACCAGAUAUGAUCCGGGAUGGAUCCACCAUUCCAAUUGCCAAAAUGUUCCAGGAGAUCGUCCACAAGAGCGUGGUGCUAAUUCCGCUGGGAGCUGUUGAUGAUGGAGAACAUUCGCAGAAUGAGAAAAUCAACAGGUGGAACUACAUAGAGGGAACCAAAUUAUUUGCUGCCUUUUUCUUAGAGAUGGCCCAGCUCCAUUAAUCACAAGAACCUUCUAGUCUGAUCUGAUCCACUGACAGAUUCACCUCCCCCACAUCCCUAGACAGGGAUGGAAUGUAAAUAUCCAGAGAAUUUGGGUCUAGUAUAGUACAUUUUCCCUUCCAUUUAAAAUGUCUUGGGAUAUCUGGAUCAGUAAUAAAAUAUUUCAAAGGCACAGAUGUUGGAAAUGGUUUAAGGUCCCCCACUGCACACCUUCCUCAAGUCAUAGCUGCUUGCAGCAACUUGAUUUCCCCAAGUCCUGUGCAAUAGCCCCAGGAUUGGAUUCCUUCAAACCUUUUAGCAUAUCUCCAACCUUGCAAUUUGAUUGGCAUAAUCACUCCAGUUUGCUUUCUAGGUCCUCAAGUGCUCGUGACACAUAAUCAUUCCAUCCAAUGAUCGCCUUUGCUUUACCACUCUUUCCUUUUAUCUUAUUAAUAAAAAUGUUGGUCUCCACCACUGACUACAAUGAUUUCCCCAUGGAUUCAUUUUCAGAGGAGUUACUAAGGCAUGGUACUAUAUUAACCUCUUGCCUCCCCUUCAUUUAUUUUUUCCCACUUCUUGAAAAGUUCCGAAGCUGAAAUGAUCAAUAUUCAUACCCAUAUGCCAUUUGGGAGUCCUUGUGCAAAGAUGAGUAUUUUUUUUUUUAUUCCAAGCUUCUUUACCUUUCCUGAGAUCGAUGCCACCUUGUCAGCUUCUCUGCCUCCCGUUCCUUCUUCCUGUCCCAUCAGAAAAGGCCCACUCUCUCUCUAUCCAACAUCUGUGCACAGGUUGCACCAGAGCAGAAUUUAUCCUGAUAGAAUUUCUCUCACCCCAUUGAAGUUUUACUCAAUGACAACAUCUAAAUUGCUCAAAGCUUUUAAUAGCAUCAGUUUUAGAUAGAGAACUAAUCAACCCUGACAUCAGUAACACACGCUAAAUUUAAAGCCAUCAGCUAAUGCUGCAUUCAUUAAUCAUUUUAGUUAACCAUCAUGUUUGGCUUGAUUGGAUUUGACGGUGUAAACAACAAAAAAAGACAGUCAUUUUUCUACAGUUGAGUGUAUAUAAACAAAAUCAAUCUUUAUGAAUUUAUUAUUUAAAUCACAUUAAUGGAGAAUCAUUUAGGGGCUUAUUAAAAUUUUUUUCUAUUAUGACUCCAAAUAAAAACAAAGCAGAGGGCCAGGCGCGGUGGCUCAUGCCCAUAAUCCCAGCACUUUCGGAGGCCGAGGUGGGCGGAUCACCUGAGGUCGGGAGUUCGAGAUCAGCCUGGCUAACAUGGUGAAACCCUGUCUCUACUGAAUAUACAAAAUUAACUGGGCAUGGUGGUGCAUGCCUGUAGUCCCAGCUACUCGGGAGGCUGAGGCAGGAGAAUCGCUUGAACCCAGGAGGCGGAAGUUGCAGUGAACUGGGAUCAUGCCACUGCACUCCAGCCUGGGCGACAGAGUGAGACUCCGUCUCCAAAAAAAAAAAAAAAAAAAAAAAAAGCAGAACACAUUUGCGUUCAACUUUUUUCCAUCACUCUGUUGGUUCUUGAGAUGUCAGUGUCAGUUUAAAAACGUGCUGUACCACCUUUAAAAGGACUGGAGCAGGCAGGCAGUGAUUCAGUUCACCUUGACUCUAGUCAUAGAAGUGGACCCAACUGAGAGCUCAACCUAGUUGUGGGCAUUUGUGAAGGAUUCCAGUUAGUGUUUUCUUUGGAAGCAGGAGGCUUCAAGCCAUCACAUCUCCAAUUCUAUAGAAUAUCAAGUCAUCGUUAAAGAACAGCAGCAGGUGUUUGAUAUUUUGUGCUAUUAAGUGUAGUUUGCGCUCAUCUAAUUAUGCAGAGUUUCGUGGUGUUUCUCGAUUUUGUUGAACCUACCUGAUGCAUUUGGCACUGUAGAUAAGGACUAACAGUAAGAGAGAUUUAGAGUCUUCAUGUUAGUCCAUUAACAUAAGUUUAUUAUAAAAUACACUGUAAGCAUUUCUGGCUAAUGUACCAUCAGAUUUAAGAAGUUACCCAACAAUAUGUAUUCGCUGAUCUUCAUUCCUGCUGAAUCUGAGACCAGCAGUGUCUCAAUUAUUACGUUGCUGCCAGGAGAGAAGGGGAGGAGAAUGAAUAGUUAUGGAAGUUGUAGAAUCUAGGAUAUUCCAACCCUGGAUUGCCAGAGUUCAGAGUCCAUGUUUUUCUGUCACCCAGGGUCACGACUGGUCUCCCCAGCUCUUCCCUCCUGUUUUUCCACCCAAUUCUAAGCCCUGUGGUGAUCCAGACCCUACCCUGACGUGGGAGUCAGAAAGGAGUAUCUUCCAAGCUCCUUGUACUCAAAGGGAUAAAAGAAAGCUACUCAGUUGUUAUUCAGAUAUAUUAACCAGCCAUAUGGAGGCAAAAAAGGGAGAAAUUUAAAUAUUUGUUUUUUAACAUUUUAAUGAUGAAAUAUAUGCACUUGGACAAAAAUGAUCACCCAGUAAAGUUGGGCGUACAUUGUGGCAUGCCCAUCAGGGGGACUUUGUUGUAUUGGAGGAGGGCAAUGUAUCUGGCUUUGUUAGUAGACGUAGCGCAUUAAAGCGUAACUAUUGUGAUAAGUUUAGGGGUUAGGAAUAUCAUUUGAGUUUGGUAGAUGCUUUUCUGGAAAACAAUGAGGCUGGGAAUGUUUCUGGCUUUAUGUUGUAUUCAUAAAAAUAAAAUGUACUGGCUUGGAAA